CGACCUCAGGUGAUCCGCCCACCUCAGCCUCCCAAAGUGCUGGGAUUACAGGUGAGAACCACCGAGCCUGGCCUCACAGCAUAGAACCUUGUAGCUACCACCUGCUACUCCAGGUGGCUCUCCCGCCUUAGUGGGUGGCAGGGGGUCCUUCCUGCUUUAGGAAUGCCCUGAGGCCUGCCUCCCUGCUCACUCCUGGCAAGAGCACAUUGUGGUGCUGUCAGGGAGGACCUCCAUGGUCUCAGAUGGAACAGCAGCAGUGGUCAGACCUCCUAGAGGCUGUGAGGUGAGGAGGAAGUGGCUGAGGUUUCCCCUGCCUCCUCCUAAGGUCAUCCAUGGGCAAACCAAAGCUGCAGGAUGUGCUGUGUGUGUGGCCUGGUAUCUCAGAGUCCUGGGUGUGCACAGGGUGUGCACAGCUAGGAGACGUCCCGAGAUCUGUACCCACAUGUUGAGGGCUUCAGCCAGGGGUGUUUUUUGGGGGAGCGGAAUUUGUGUGGCAUAGUAGAGGAAAAGAAGGAAGAAGUGGGGACAGUAUCUCCAGCUGCCACCUUUCUUCCCAAAUAGCUUUGGAUACCCAGGCCCUUUUGGUCACAGGAAGUCUGACACUGGGAAGUCAUCAAAUUUGGAAUUCAGUUCCCUCCACUCUCCCCCCAGCGGUGGCCUUAGCAUUUAAAUAGCCUUGGCAUGAAGCCCUAUAAACUGCCCAAGGGAUUGGGGCAGGGUUAGGGGGAGGGGUAUUGGUGUUACCCCCAACAUUGUCCCCCUGUGUCUUCUGGGGACAUGUCCAAGCUAGGGUGUCAGUGUUUUGGCUUGAGAGGAGAGAGGGGAAGGGGCCACAGACUGGGCAGGAGCCCUCCUGGCUCCCCUCCCGCUCUGGUGGUUUUGAUCGUAAUCCCUGCCUGCCAAGCCUGGAGCUCCCUGGGGGAUCCGCCCCAGAGGAGGCCCGACUGUUCUCCUCCCCUCUGCCUUACCUCCCCCAGUCCCCGCCCCCUGCUUGACUCAGAAUGGAAUGUGCAGCCUGUGGAACAAGAUGGGGUGAGAACUAGUUCCCAGAGGGCCUUGGUCCCGCCCCUCCCAUCCCCCAACAAAGGGGGUGAGGAACCUGGAGGCAGGGCCUGCUCCCAGGAUGUCCAUGAGGAGCCCCAUCUCUGCCCAGCUGGCCCUGGAUGGCGUUGGCACCAUGGUGAACUGCACCAUCAAGUCAGAGGAGAAGAAAGAGCCUUGCCACGAGGCCCCCCAGGGCUCAGCCACUGCCGCUGAACCUCAGCCUGGAGACCCAGCCCGGGCCUCCCAGGAUAGUGCUGACCCCCAAGCUCCAGCCCAGGGGAAUUUCAGGGGCUCCUGGGACUGUAGCUCUCCAGAGGGUAAUGGGUCCCCAGAACCCAAGAGACCAGGAGUGUCGGAGGCUGCCUCUGGAAGCCAGGAGAAGCUGGACUUCAACCGAAAUUUGAAAGAAGUGGUGCCAGCCAUAGAGAAGCUGUUGUCCAGUGACUGGAAGGAGAGGUUUCUAGGAAGGAACUCUAUGGAAGCCAAAGAUGUCAAAGGGACCCAAGAGAGCCUAGCAGAGAAGGAGCUCCAGCUUCUGGUCAUGAUUCACCAGCUGUCCACCCUGCGGGACCAGCUCCUGACAGCCCACUCGGAGCAGAAGAACAUGGCUGCCAUGCUGUUUGAGAAGCAGCAGCAGCAGAUGGAGCUUGCCCGGCAGCAGCAGGAGCAGAUUGCAAAGCAGCAGCAGCAGCUGAUUCAGCAGCAGCAUAAGAUCAACCUCCUUCAGCAGCAGAUCCAGCAGGUUAACAUGCCUUAUGUCAUGAUCCCAGCCUUCCCCCCAAGCCACCAACCUCUGCCUGUCACCCCUGACUCCCAGCUGGCCUUACCCAUUCAGCCCAUUCCCUGCAAACCAGUGGAGUAUCCGCUGCAGCUGCUGCACAGCCCCCCUGCCCCAGUGGUGAAGAGGCCUGGGGCCAUGGCCACCCACCACCCCCUGCAGGAGCCCUCCCAGCCCCUGAACCUCACAGCCAAGCCCAAGGCCCCCGAGCUGCCCAACACCUCCAGCUCCCCAAGCCUGAAGAUGAGCAGCUGUGUGCCCCGCCCCCCCAGCCAUGGAGGCCCCACGCGGGACCUGCAGUCCAGCCCCCCGAGCCUGCCUCUGGGCUUCCUUGGUGAAGGGGACGCUGUCACCAAAGCCAUCCAGGAUGCUCGGCAGCUGCUGCACAGCCACAGUGGGGCCUUGGAUGGCUCCCCCAACACCCCCUUCCGUAAGGACCUCAUCAGCCUGGACUCAUCCCCAGCCAAGGAGCGGCUGGAGGACGGCUGUGUGCACCCACUGGAGGAAGCCAUGCUGAGCUGCGACAUGGAUGGCUCCCGCCACUUCCCCGAGUCCCGAAACAGCAGCCACAUCAAGAGGCCCAUGAACGCCUUCAUGGUGUGGGCCAAGGAUGAGCGGAGGAAGAUCCUGCAAGCCUUCCCAGACAUGCACAACUCCAGCAUCAGCAAGAUCCUUGGAUCUCGCUGGAAGUCCAUGACCAACCAGGAGAAGCAGCCCUACUAUGAGGAACAGGCGCGGCUGAGCCGGCAGCACCUGGAGAAGUAUCCUGACUACAAGUACAAGCCGCGGCCCAAGCGCACCUGCAUCGUGGAGGGCAAGCGGCUGCGCGUGGGAGAGUACAAGGCCCUGAUGAGGACCCGGCGUCAGGAUGCCCGCCAGAGCUACGUGAUCCCCCCGCAGGCUGGCCAGGUGCAGAUGAGCUCCUCAGAUGUCCUGUACCCUCGGGCAGCAGGCAUGCCGCUGGCACAGCCACUGGUGGAGCACUAUGUCCCUCGUAGCCUGGACCCCAACAUGCCUGUGAUCGUCAACACCUGCAGCCUCAGAGAGGAGGGUGAGGGCACAGAUGACAGGCACUCGGUGGCUGAUGGCGAGAUGUACCGGUACAGCGAGGACGAGGACUCGGAGGGCGAAGAGAAGAGCGAUGGGGAGUUGGUGGUGCUCACAGACUGAUCCCGGCUGGGUGGGCCUGGCCCCUUCUCCUCUGGGGAAGACCUUGUCCCAACUCGAUGGGCACAGCCAGCCAACCUAAGACUAUGUUGGUACUUGGACUUGUUCGUGCCCCAGAGAUGGGCAAAGCUGUGCACUUGCAGAUACAUUCAUGAGGGGAGAGGCGCCCUCCCUUCCUGAGGAGCUGUUGGCCUGGGUGGGCAGGAACUGCAGUAUGGCCAUGGGCUGAGCAGGCUGAGCACCUCAGCCUUUAGGGCUUAUGGCCAGGGGACACUGUAUGACUCUCCUCUCCUGCAGGUGUCUAUCCACCUGGGGUAUGGCAUCUACCGACCUGUCUCCCUGGGGUCACAUGCUUUGUUUCCAUUCUUGUCCUGGCUGGACCAGCCACUGUGGGACCAACACCCCUCCCACACUCCCCCAGACUGCUCGUCUAUCACCAGGAUCGCUUUGUACUUUGUGCAAAAGGGUCUGGCUGUCCCUUGCUGUUUUCAUCUCUGCCAAGCCUAUUGUGCCUCUGGCUGCUGUAUGUGUGCGCGUGCACGUGUGUGUGUUUCAUCUGUUCAUUCACUGCACAAGAUAUUUAUUGAGUGCCCACUACGUGCCAGGCACUGUUGCUGAGUUCCUGUGGGUGUGUCUCUCGAUGCCACUCCUGCUUCUCUGGGGGCCUCUUUCUGUGCUUCUCUUUGUCCCCAAAUUGCUACCUCUUUGUCAGUCUGGGUGUCUCAGGUUCUGUGUGUCCUUGUGUGCAUUUCUGUCUCUCUCUGUCCUCGUCUCUCUGCAAGGCCCUCUAUUUCUCUCUUUCUUGGUGUCUGUCCUUUGCCCCCUGUGCCCUCUGGAUUCUCUGGGUCUAUGUAGGCCCCUGGUCUGCCCUGGGCUCAUCAGCCUUCCUGACCUCCUCCUGCCCUCCCCUUCACUCCCUCCCUGGCUCUGCCAGUCGGUUCCCACGGAGCCAUUUUUAGCUCUGAUCAGCAUGGGAAUGUGCCUCGGCCUCCAAGGGGCUUUGUCCUGGUGCCCCCGCCCCUGGUCCCAACCUGAUCCCACGAGGGAGUUGGGACAGGAGGAUUGAUGGUGCUCCCCUUCCUGCCAGCGUCAGAGGCCCUGGAGAGGGGCUGUCCAUGGCAGCUGGUCUUUAUUCCUCCCUCAUGAGCACAGGGUCGGGGGGGUCCCCAUUCUUGGAAGAGGUUGAGAAGACUCCUGGGCUUCAGCCUCUCCCACCCAGCCCUGCCCCUCACCUGCCUGCCCUCCCCUCCCCCACUCUAUACUAGGGACUGGAUCUCAGCCUCUGAUCAGUUUCACAAAGUUUGUUCCCUAAGGAAAUCAAAUCCCAUUGUCACCUAACUCUGAAGAUCUAAAUAGCCCUUGGAUCAGUAUGGGAACCCCAAAUCCCACAGGGCCAGAUGUGGAGUCUGUGUCUGCCCCCGUCUUCUCUCCAUCCUCAAAGCCCCCACUUCUCUCCAGGCUGUUUCUUUUUUUAUGACUGUAAACAUAGAUAGUGCUUUAUUUUGUUAAUAAUAAGAUAAUGAUGAGUAACUUAACCAGCACAUUUCUCCUGUUUACACUCGGGGGAUUUUUUUGUUUUCUGAUGACAUAAUAAAGACAGAUCAUUUCAGAA